AGGCCCGAGAGUGACCGGAGUCACGGCGGGCGCCGGCGGAGCUGCGGCGUCGGACCCGCCUCCUGGAGGAGCUCAGCCCCGACCAGGCCCGGCCCCAUUCCCGCCCCGCGCCGCCUCCCCGCCGCCGCCGCCGCCGCCGCCGCGGGAGCGCUCCCCUGCCCACCCCGCCCCCGCGGCCGAGCCCGGGAGUCGAGUGGGAGUCGGCCGGCCGGCGCGGGCAGCGCCGGGACCCCGCGGGGGACACUGCAGCCGGAGCCCGGGAGGGGCCGCGCCGCCACCGUCUGAACUAGGAUGUCCCGACAUGAAGGCCAGAGGUCCCUGUUGCUGUGCAUAUAUUAUUAGCCGAGUAUAUGAUGGGAAGGCUUUCUAAACAGCUCUUAGACCCUGUUUUCAGUGCUCAGUGGUACACAGUCUUUGCAUUGCCUGUGUCAGCUGUGAUGCAUGUUUAAAAGGAAAUUUUCGAGGUCGCAGAUAUAAGUGUUUAAUUUGCUACGAUUACGAUCUUUGUGCAUCUUGUUAUGAAAGUGGUGCAACAACAACAAGGCAUACAACUGACCACCCAAUGCAGUGCAUAUUAACAAGGGUAGAUUUUGAUUUAUACUAUGGUGGGGAAGCUUUCUCUGUAGAGCAGCCACAGUCUUUUACUUGUCCCUAUUGUGGAAAAAUGGGCUAUACGGAGACAUCUCUUCAAGAACAUGUUACUUCUGAACAUGCAGAAACAUCAACAGAAGUGAUUUGUCCAAUAUGUGCAGCGUUACCUGGAGGCGAUCCUAAUCAUGUCACGGAUGACUUUGCAGCUCAUCUUACACUUGAACACAGAGCCCCUAGAGAUUUAGAUGAAUCGAGUGGUGUUCGACAUGUACGUAGAAUGUUUCACCCUGGCCGGGGAUUAGGAGGUCCUCGUGCUCGUAGAUCAAACAUGCACUUUACUAGCAGUUCUACUGGUGGACUUUCUUCUUCUCAGAGUUCAUAUUCUCCAAGCAAUAGGGAAGCCAUGGAUCCUAUAGCUGAGCUUUUAUCUCAGUUAUCAGGAGUGAGACGUUCUGCAGGAGGACAGCUUAAUUCCUCUGGCCCUUCCGCUUCUCAGUUACAACAACUGCAGAUGCAGCUGCAGCUAGAACGGCAGCAUGCCCAGGCAGCACGGCAACAACUGGAGACCGCACGCAACGCAACCCGGCGUACUAACACAAGCAGUGUCACCACUACAAUCACACAAUCCACAGCAACAACCAACAUAGCUAAUACAGAAAGCAGUCAGCAGACUCUACAGAAUUCCCAGUUUCUUUUAACAAGGUUGAAUGAUCCUAAAAUGUCUGAAACGGAGCGCCAGUCCAUGGAAAGCGAGCGUGCAGACCGCAGCCUGUUUGUCCAAGAGCUCCUUCUGUCCACUUUAGUGCGUGAAGAGAGCUCAUCCUCAGAUGAGGAUGAUCGGGGGGAGAUGGCAGAUUUUGGUGCUAUGGGCUGUGUAGAUAUUAUGCCUUUAGAUGUUGCUUUAGAAAACCUAAAUUUAAAAGAGAGUAAUAAAGGAAAUGAGCCUCCACCACCUCCUCUUUGAUGACAUCCCAAUUCGCAGACAAUGUCCUCUGUGCUGUAUUUGCCAAUGAAAGUGGACAACAACUAUCUUGGGUUUGUUUGGUGAUUGUAAUUUCAGGUCUGUCACUCUUGUUACAUUGUGUACAUUCAAAAGGAAGAGAGAAAAUAUAUAUGAUAAUCAUUUCCACUUAACUAAUUUUUACUUCUAGCAGGUAAAUGUAGGUAGCAGUGCAGGGGUGAUCUCUGCUUCCUGUACCUUGACAUGCAAAAGGCUCUCCUAAUACUCCACAUUCAAACUGAAGAGGAAAAUUGAAAUCUCUAAUGAAGCUGCUGUGUGUAUUUAUGAAUAUUAAUGAAUAAAAACUGCUUGGAUGGUUUACCUUAACUACUGCAUGAGGUUUUUUGCAGCGUGCAUGAGUUUUAGUGACCUUGUUAUUUAAGAAGUUAAAUACAAGGAGUAAAACUUAAAAAAAAAAUACAAAGCCCAAAGCUUUCCCAAACAUUAUUCAAUGGUUACACGACGAAGUAGCUUUUGAAUAAUGUCUGCCUGAAUCACCUUUCUUUGUGUGCCUCCUACGCACAAAGCCAGCUCUGCAGUGGAAUCUGGGGAUUAUAGCCGGGUGUGGCACUCCGCCCUGUGUGACUGUCCUGUCGCCCUGUUAGUCAUCUUGCCUGUGUGGAGCUCAGCCUGUCUCUUUAACUCAUCUGUAGAAGACACACCAGUAAAGCUACUGUUGGAAUCUGCUGCAGGGGCCUUUGUGUGCCCUAAAAACAAAUCCUGUUCAUGUUUGUUUAAAGUUUUUACUUUUUGUGGUUGUUUAAAAUUUUUUCAAUUGUUAAAUAUGUUUUAUUCAGGUGUAGAUGAAUUUCAUUUAUUGACUGUUCAACAGAGUUAACCUGAAUUAUGUUGUCUUUGUUUUUAAAAAUCUCACAUUCUCAAUCAUAUUUUGCAUUAUUUAUGUAUUUGCUUUGUAGUUUGCUGAGACAGAUCAGUAUCAGGGGAGCUUUGAGGAUUUGCCUUCCCAGAUUUGUCAGUAUAUUACAACCAAAUUCUUAAUGCUAAUUUUAGCACCUUUUAUUUAUUGGGUUUUUUCUGGCAUAAAAAGUAAAGCCUUUUAAUUGAAUCAUGCCACCUAUAUGCCUAUAUUAUUAAUCCUAUGUGUAAAAAAAAUGUACAGCUUUUUUUGGGUUUGUUUUGGGGUUUGGAAGGGCCGGGUUAUUUUUUAUUUCCUGUUUCAGUUUUUGUGCAUAGACUUUCACAAUAGCUCCAAGGCAGGGACAGCGGGUUUGGGGGUUGGGAGGGCAGUUUUUGGAAUGUAAAUUUAGGACUUUUAAAAAGGUGCGCACAGCUUCUGAUAAAUUUAUAACUAGACUUAACCUAAUCAUGUCUCGUUCCAGUUCUCUUUUCUCUGAGCCCUUUUCAAAGUCUCCUCUCUUUCUCCUGUCAUCCUUUUCCUUUCCUGUCCGUGUAUCUCCGUUUCUUCAACAUGACAAGCAUACAGACUUGAACACCCCUCCGGUGUUCUUCCGAGAACUGUGAAGUCCAUGUUCAUCCAAAUGUAACCAAAAAAGAAGUCACCCUACAUGUCUGAAAAACUGUUGCUUCUCCUCUGAAACUUCAAACUCCAACGAUUUCCAAAUACAAUAGCUUUGUUUUCUUUAGUUCUGUAAUGGAUAAUGUUUAAAGGAAAACUUUACACCAGGCUUCUGGUUACACUAGAAGUCAAGCCCAUUAGGGAUUUUCAUUUUUUUUCAUUUGGUUGUUGAGAAGUUUCAAAAAUCAGUUUUCAAGCUGUGGUCUUUCAAACACAUCUGCACAUAAGUCACACAUUUCAAUAAAGCAUUUUCAAGACUGUUGACCACUUGAAUUUCUUUGGUGUUAGUGGAUUAACCUAACCAUUACUCUGAGAUUUUAUAUCUCUAAUCCAGUAUUUUUUUUCUUUUUAUGCUAAACAUGGGAGAUCCUGGUUUUGUGUGAAUGCAUUAUUUUGGAUGUGAGAAAUAAAUGCCAAUUAUAUGUACUUUCCCUUUUCUGCACAAAUUCUGGGAAAAUGUAAAAGCCUUCAUUUUUUAACAUGGUUUUAGGGAACAACUGUAAGUCCAUUCAGAGCAGUUUAAUUUAGAUGAUCACUUUUAACACUGCAGAAGACCUAAGGAGUCAUAAGAUUCCAUCUCAUGUAGAAUACUGUAUAUUAAUUAUUUUUUACCAGAUAUUUUACAAAUACCUCACCUCAUCCUGUAUGUAAUCAAUAAUGUAUUAUUUUAGGGUAGAACGACACAGAAUAUCAAUAUAAAAAUAUAUUCAAGCCCUUGAAAUUCUUGUGUCCUUUUUCUUUAGUUUCUGAAUGAAAAUCUUAUUACUGGAUGUACUAUUGAAUAAAAAUUAAUUGCAAAGACUUUGAUGGAGACAAAAUCAAAAUAUACCACUGUUUAUUUUGGCAGCACCUUCAAAUUUCUAAGGACCAGAUCCUGAAUUUUGAGAAUUUUUUGUUUCGUUGAGUUUUGAGUGUCUAGGAUAUAAGUUUAUAAAUGUUCUACAGUGCUUGUCUUUACUUCCUGUUUAGAAAUCAUUUAAAUCUUUCCCCUCGAGGUGCUCUGGAAGAAGUUUAAUUUCAGCUCUGAACAAGUAGAAAUAACUGUGCUUCCUUGUAUGGCUGCAAUCAUAAGACAGAAUUUCUGUGGUUGGCUACCGUGAAAUCUUUGUAUUUAUAUUGCAUUGUUUUGUUAAAAAAAAAAAAAUCCACAGAAGUAGAACCUAGGUUUGCUACUAACAAAGUAGUGGAUUCUUAUAAUUAGGCUCAGGUAAAGUAAGAGAAAACUUCUCUCCCUGUGGCCCCCAGAGAAAUGAAGUAGGAUAGCAGAUUACACUAUUAGAAAUAAUAGACGUAACAAAAAAAAUCCAGCCCAUUAUCCCCACCCCCCAUUUUCCCUCUCAAUAUUAGAAAUUUCAAUAAUAUGCUGACAGAUUUUCAAAGGUCACCAAGGCUUUUGUGUUUUUUUCCGGUCUGUGGGCCACAGUUAAAAGAACGGGUAACAGGUUCAGAGUUCUCUUGAUACGUCCAAGCCUUAGUUUCCAGGAAAAAAGCUAGGCUCCUCACUGCAAAUAUUAACGCUUUAUAUAUUUACUCCAUGGAUGUUGGGGUAAGCACAUAUAUCAAUAGUUCAUAGCUCUAGUUAAGGACAAAGUGGGUUGGGGGGUAGAAGGAGAAUACUAGAGAGGUUACGGUAGCAGGUGGCUGCAGAAAAGAAUCUUUUGAAUGGGAUUCCUGUAACAGUGUUCAGUACCAAUAUUAAGUCUACUGUAAGUGGGGUCUGAUAUGGCUUACUGAUACAGGCAUGUGUAAAAAACUAAGUGUGAUGGAGGAAUGGGUGCUAAAAGCUCUUAACAGUUUUGUAGAGAAGCCCUGCAGCCGUGUUUACUAUAUAUGACAUGCCUGUUUCUUAGUUUGCAUGCACAGUUUAAGGGGCACAUGCAAUAUUGGUUUCAUGUGCAGUAAAAAUUAAAACACGGCUGAGCGUGGUGGCUCACGCCUGUAAUCCCAGCACUUUGCGAGGCCGAGGCGGGUGGAUCACGAGGUCGAGUUUGAGACCAUUUUGGCCAGCAUAGUGAAACCCCAUCUCUACUAAAAAAUACAAAAAGUUAGCUGGGCAUGGUGGCAGGCACCUGUAAUCCCAGCUACUCGGGAGGCUGAGGCAGGAGAAUCGCUUGAACCUGGGAGGCAGAGGUUGCAGUGAGCUGAGAUCACGCCGCCAUUGCACUCCAGCCCGGGCGACGGUGCAAGACUCUGUCUCAAAAAAAAAAAAAAUUAAAACACUAGGUACGAAAUUAUCCCAGAAUUAUACGCGAAAGUUGGUGUUCAUGCUGGAAAACAGUUACGGUUAUCUGUGCUCUUUCUAAAGCUCAACUAGACACUAAAACAGUUCUCUCCUUGAGACCGGAAGUGGGAUGGGGGUGGGCAGGUGGAAGGGAAGAGGCUGGGGAGGAGCCUCUCAUCUCAUCUCAUUUCAGCCUCAACAGUAAUUGAAACCCUAUGCCUGGCCUGGAGUGGGUAGAGGUUAGGGUUAGAGUGCAGGAUGGAGCAGCAGUCUGCAGACUUUCAGGUUGUGACGAUGUCAUGAAAUUCUGUGCUAUUAAACAUGGCUAUGUCUGAGUCAGUCAUUACGGUAUUCCAAAGCCAAAUUCAAGUGACUGUUUUUCUGAAUAGUAUAAAAAUCUAAUUCCCUGUGCUUAUCGGCUUCAACUGUGCUUACACAACGUUUGUUUCUAAUUCGUACUCUUGCCUCUUGGUUUCUGUAGUUUUUCAACCCAUUUCUGUCAGUGUUCUAUAAAUGCAUACAUUCGUUAUUUAAGGAACCCUGCAGCAGACCUCGAAUAAAAUGUGACUUGAUGUUUGUUGCCACUUCCUCAACUUGGUUAGCAAAUUCAAGUUUUGAAAGACGAUUCGUCUCAGAGAAGUUGAUCCUGAACCUCCACGUCACAUUUUAGUCGGUUGCUAUUAGGUGGGUAAUGCCUAAUAACAUGGGUUCCUCAAAUCACAAAGGAGAAUGCUCUCAAGUCCUCAUGUUAACUUUAGUAAGUCAGUUAACUUUACAGCAACUAAAGAGAUCAAUUAAAAAGAACCCUUAAGUCUGACUGUCCCAGGUAACUUUACUUGCUGUACAGAUAGUGCACAGAUAUGGAUGAGGGCUGCACAUGGCUGAUUUGAAAACCCAUGUGGGGCCGGGUGUGGUGGCUCACGCCUGUAAUCCCAGCACUUUGGGAGGCCAAGGCGGGUGGAUCACGAGGUUAGUUCAGGACCAGCCUGGCCAAGAUGGUGAAACCCCAUCUCUACUAAAAAUACGAAAAUUAGCUGGGCUUGGUGGCAGAUGCCUGUAAUUCCUGCUACUCGGGAGGCUGAGGCAGAGAAUUGCUUGAACCCGGGAGGCGGAGGUUGCAGUGAGCCGAGAUUGCGCCACUGCACUCCAGCCUGGGCGACACAGUGAGACUCUCCUCAAAACAAAAAAAAAAGAAAGAAAACCCAUGUGGGCCGCAUGUGCACAGCCUGGGGCUGCUUUCCACAGGCCUGGAUAAUGAUGUUUCUCUUCAAGGAGGCCUUUACUAACCACAGGGAACCUAGCAUCUGACUGUGUCCUUGGCAGACAGUGCAUGUAGCCUGUAGAAUGUUGGCUCCUCUGUCUAUAGAAACCAUCAGUUCGCUGCUCUCUCAUUCAUACAUACUUUUUGAGUUCCCAGUAGGUACGAAGCUUUGUCUAAACAUUAUUUACCAACUGCGAUUUUUACAGACUUCCCCUGUAAGAAUUUUCUAAAAGAGCCUUUCUCCCUUACACAAUUGAAACGUUUUCAAAGGUCAUCAAGCCGGUUGCGUUUGGUCAGUCACGUGACCAAUCAGAGCUGGUGAGUGAGCUGCUCCCUUAAAUCUACCAAAUUAGACUGACAGCAUUUGGAAUCUGCCUCACACAUAAGAGAUCCAUAUUCAUUUAAUAGUGAAGCCAGCCCAGAAGCAUCCUCUUCUGUAAGCUGGAUGGAGUCCCAGCUCUCUCUCCUUGUAUAUAAGGAGACCACACCCUGUAUAUAAGGUUUUCUUGAGGUAGAUGCAGCAAUAUUCCUGGGGUAAGAUUCUAUAAUACUCCUGUAUUGGCAAGUGGACUGGACCAACAGACACAGGCCUCAGCCACUGUCGCUAGGGACUGAAGGAGAGUUCAUGGAUUCUUACCCCCUAGUCAUGAAAGCUAUUCUGGCCAGCCUUGAAUCCAUUUAAUUUUGCCCACGAGAACCUUUCAUGACAAUUAACAAGACACUAGUUUCCCCAUAAAAGUCCAUUUUUAAAUAUAUAGUAUGCUAAUUAGCAGUGUCUGUUGAAUUGCCCUAUCGGAUAGCAGCCACCAUGUGUGCUGACCACUCACGAUUCAGACUUACCUUGGAAAAUAUCACACUGACGAUACAGUACUUUAGAAUAAAUUGCAUAUUGUAUCAGGCUCCGAGACUAAUUUGUACUGAACCCUUGAUAUAGAUUACCUUUUAUAACAUCACCACCUGUCAUGAAGCUUAUCUGUUUUCUGAUUUGAAUAAACUUUGUGUUGUGCA